AGUACAGCUCCAGCACAAUGAUUCCCAUGCUGCAGAGGGAGAGGACAACAGCUCCAGUAAACAAAAAGGUCAGGGCAGACAGGAGUAUUAUGGAACUGCUCCAGGACUCUUGAUUUUCAAGCUUAUCUGCAAUGCAUCUAGAACUUAUCUUGGUGUAUGGUAUGAGAUGGUGUCAGGAAUGGGAUCUAAAGUGGAGCUUCUAGCGACCCCCAGGAGCACUGAGUGAACAUGCAAGGUACCUGCAGGAUCCACUUGUGUCUAUUGAUCUCUCACAGCAGCUGGGGAUCACAGAACCUGCAGAUUGGAUCGUCUGAGAACACCAGAGAAAGAGAAAGACUGUCCUUGCCAUCCACACUACAGCAAAACUUUGGAGCUUUAAACCUUGGGUUCAUAAUCUCACAGCUGAGAAGGGUCCCUCCACACUCCUGGAACUGUACAUCCAUUGGAACCCUUAAGGAAUCAUUGUAGUCAAUCAUUUUCCAGUUCUCAGCCGCUCAGUUGUGAUCAAGGGACACGUGGUUUCCGAACUGCCAGCUCAGAAUAGGAAAAUAACUUGGGAUUUUAUAUUGGAAGACAUGGAUCUUGCUGCCAACGAGAUCAGCAUUUAUGACAAACUUUCAGAGACUGUUGAUUUGGUGAGACAGACCGGCCAUCAGUGUGGCAUGUCAGAGAAGGCAAUUGAAAAAUUUAUCAGACAGCUGCUGGAAAAGAAUGAACCUCAGAGACCCCCCCCGCAGUAUCCUCUCCUUAUAGUUGUGUAUAAGGUUCUCGCAACCUUGGGAUUAAUCUUGCUCACUGCCUACUUUGUGAUUCAACCUUUCAGCCCAUUAGCACCUGAGCCAGUGCUUUCUGGAGCUCACACCUGGCGCUCACUCAUCCAUCACAUUAGGCUGAUGUCCUUGCCCAUUGCCAAGAAGUACAUGUCAGAAAAUAAGGGAGUUCCUCUGCAUGGGGGUGAUGAAGACAGACCCUUUCCAGACUUUGACCCCUGGUGGACAAACGACUGUGAGCAGAAUGAGUCAGAGCCCAUUCCUGCCAACUGCACUGGCUGUGCCCAGAAACACCUGAAGGUGAUGCUCCUGGAAGACGCCCCAAGGAAAUUUGAGAGGCUCCAUCCACUGGUGAUCAAGACGGGAAAGCCCCUGUUGGAGGAAGAGAUUCAGCAUUUUUUGUGCCAGUACCCUGAGGCGACAGAAGGCUUCUCUGAAGGGUUUUUCGCCAAGUGGUGGCGCUGCUUUCCUGAGCGGUGGUUCCCAUUUCCUUAUCCAUGGAGGAGACCUCUGAACAGAUCACAAAUGUUACGUGAGCUUUUUCCUGUUUUCACUCACCUGCCAUUUCCAAAAGAUGCCUCUUUAAACAAGUGCUCCUUUCUUCACCCAGAACCUGUUGUGGGGAGUAAGAUGCAUAAGAUGCCUGACCUAUUUAUCAUUGGCAGCGGUGAGGCCAUGUUGCAGCUCAUCCCUCCCUUCCAGUGCCGAAGACAUUGUCAGUCUGUGGCCAUGCCAAUAGAGCCAGGGGAUAUCGGCUAUGUCGACACCACCCACUGGAAGGUCUACGUUAUAGCCAGAGGGGUCCAGCCUUUGGUCAUCUGCGAUGGAACCGCUUUCUCAGAACUGUAGGAAAUAGAACUGUGCACAGGAACAGCUUCCAGAGCCGAAAACCAGGUUGAAAGGGGAAAAAUAAAAACAAAAACGAUGAAACUGCUUUCUGGGGGUUGGUUACUUAGUUACCUGCCCUUUGCAUGCAUGUGUGAACCAGCUGUGAGCUGCAAGGCAGUGGCCAGAGCCUCGCCCUCCUGACUCUUCCUGCAGGUGGCUCAGGAAGGAUUCAGCCUGGCCACUUGGCUAGGACUCUGCCAGCACCCAUCUGAGACUGACCUCUUCCGGGCCUUUGGACACUAUGACCUUGAUGCUGCCCUUCAGGCAGGAAACAGGGCUGGUGCCUUUCUUCACCUGCAUGGCCAGCUUCCUUCCCUGGCAGUGGAGAGGGCAGCCAACAGGUUCUAAUGUCAGAGCCAUCCUUUACCAGGUGGGCCUGCUUGUCCCUGUCUUGCCUGCCACAUCACUCUACUUUUUGGAAGGCCAUGGCUGAUUAAAGAAGUUCUUGUAGUUUCCCAAGCAAAGUGGAAUCUAGAAACAGUGAAAAAAGUUCAGAUAACUUUGAAUUGCAUUCAAGAAGUACACUUCUUUCCCAUUGUCCGUGGCUCUUGGAGUCUCCGUGAUGCCAGGCUAGAGUCUGAUUAUAUAAUAAUUCAAAAUGGUAACUCCCAAGGUAAUGCUUUCUUCCAUUUCAUCAGGUUCUUUUAUCCCCACUGCACCCCCUCCCCUUCUCCCUUGCCUAUCUGGAUGGCUUCUCAGAAGCUCGGCCCUAGUCCUCCCUGCCUUGGCGGGGCCAGAGCCCACUACUGCUGAGGCAGCACUGCUCUCGUCAGCUGUGUUGCCUUUACCAAGUGUCUUCAGAGGGUUAUGAGUUAGAGUAGCUGGCCUGGGGAGAGGGUGCCUCCCUGGGUUUGAUCUUUAGGGUCUGACUUUCUGCAGAGAAGAUGUUUUACAGAUGUGUCAAAGCUGAUGUAAUGUGGUUGGGGGAGGAAAUCCAGACCCAAAGUGUUUGUCAGCUGGGUGUACAACUGCCUAUGUGAUCCUCUGUCUUAAAAUGAUUUCUGUCUGUGCUGCGAAACAAAGACAAGGUGAGGUGUUUUUCUUUUUUGUAAUAAUAUAAAGCUGUGUGUUUCUGAUUGGAUGAUUCACUAUGUGCAUUGUUUUCUCCUAAGUGCUUUUAGUAGGUAGCAAUCAAAUGGUGUAAAUAAGGAUGUUCUUUUCCUGUUCCUUUUAUUUUUUUCUCUCUUUAUUAUUCUUUUAUUGACACCACUAGAUAGCUGGCCACUGGUCAUGCCAUUGCCAAGAUGAAGAAAAAGCAAACUACACUUUGGCCUCUGGUUCUGAAUUGCAGAAAUCAAAGGAUGCAGUAGGUGUCUAUGUCAGAAUUAUGGAUCAGAGGCAGACAAUGACGAGUGAAGAUGGUUGUGAAGCCCUCUUCAUUCCUGGAGGAGCCUGCAUCUCAUCUCUCAGGCCCUCUUUCUCUGUGGGUCUCAUGAACAGCAGUGGGGACCAUUGAGCACUUGAAUGGCCUGUUUGUCUAUGGGCUUGCAAAGGACAAGCAGAGUUCACAGAGCUCAGGAUAGAAACAUCAGAGCCUCCUCCACGGGCUUCAGUGAAACUCCGAUGAACUGUACCUGAGGGAAUUUUUUCUUAAUCAACCCCUUGUGUGGAUGAAUACAGGAACAACAAAACUUGUGUACGUAUGAAAGUCAUGUUGUUAAGCAGUUAUGAUUUAAGAGGUUUUAAGUCAGAGGGAUCAUCUGGAGGCCGGCUUUGUGCAAGCUUUUACAGCCUUCUGCAGUGUCCUUACCCUGGCUGUACAUGGGGAAGGGCUAUGUGUAAACAAGUGCUUUAGAGGCCUCUGAGAGUUUUUAAAAAUCAGACCCAUUAACAAAAGAGAGGGUUUCUUAGGAACAAAGCAACUAUUUUGAUUACUGAGAUCUCUGUUUUGUUUCUGUGAGUUACUCUGUAUUCCUUUCCCCAUUUCACUCUUGCCCUUCACAUCUUAAAUGUCCAUAAGAAACCCUUGCAUGUGUUGGUAUUCUGAGGCAUCCCGUGGGAAAGUCCCCUAAGUCCCAUUUUGUACUUCAACAAAAAAUGACUGUAGCAGAAGAUAAGUGGAGACUUUUAUGGAUAUACUACUCAUUUUACUUAAAAUCUACCCAGUUCAGACUUGAAUGUAAACUUGUAUUAGGGGAAAAUUCUCCAAAGAGGGUUUUCUACAUACACAGAAGCAGUUCAACUUCUCAAGUUAAUUUUGAUAAGCAGAAUCUACUACUGGCCAGAGCGACAGGAGUGGCUAGGGGUUGCCAGCCAGUCCCUUUCUGAUGAUCAAGGCCCUGCACAGCAGGAUGCCACAGGAUGCCCCUGCCAUCUAGCUGGAAGCAUCAAAAGUCCCUCUGUAUGACCCGGUGUGGGAAAGAGGGUUGUCAGGAUGAGAAAGUGGGGCUGCAGGGUGACGAUAAGACCACCUAACCAACUCCCCACCUCCACCACCACAAUAAGAACAAAACUGUAGGGCUCUAAAGAGAGGGGGUGGUUUACAAGUUUAUUGAGCAUUUACUAGGAAGUGACAUGGCGAUGACCUCUGUACAUGAGUUAGGUUCACUUUCAUGUGGCCUCCCACUACAGAGAUGCGUAUGCCCAGAAGUCAGCUCUCUGAGGAGACAGGCUACUUUGGCCCCAGUUUGAAGCAUUCUGUCCAAAUGUCCUGAGCUCUCCAGCAGUCAAGUAGUGAAUGGAUACCAUACUUAUUAUGGUUGAUGAAAAAAGGCAGAGCUUAUCCUCAAUUUUUUUUAGGGAAGAGAAGGAAUAAAAUAAAAGUGGUUCAAGCUGGGCAUGGUGGCUCACACCUGUAAUUGCAGCACUUUGGGAGGCUGAGGCAGGCAGAUCACUUGAGGUCAGGAGUUCAAGACCAGCCUGGCCAACAGGGUGAAACCCCAUCUCUACUAAAAAUACAAAAAUUACCCAGGCGUGAUGGUGGGCGCCUGUAAUCCCAGCUACACAGGAAGCUGAGGCAGGAAAAUUGCUUGAACCGGGGAGGCGGAGAUUGCAGUGAGCCAAGAUUGUGCCACUUCAUUCCAGCCUGGGCGACAGAGCGAAACUCUGUCAAAGGAAAGGAAAGAAAAGAAAAAAAAAAAGAGAGAGAGAAAAGAAGAGGGGAGGGGAGGGAAAGGGAAGGGAGGGGAGGGGAGGAGAGGAGAGCAGAUUGGGGGGGCUCAUGUUCUGAGAGAAAGGAAUAAUAGCAUUUGUCUAGUACAUUCCAGUUUACAAAGUGCCUGAUAUACAUGAUCUCCUUUAAUCUUCACCCAAUCCUGUAAAGUAGGUGUUAGAUCCCCAUUUUGCAAGUAAAUAAGUGGAGGCUUAGAGCAGUUAACCGCUGGCAGGUAGGUAGCUGGUUCCAUAGCACAUCAUUUUCCUGCGGCAUCACGGCAUGGUGCCGAAGAAGACAGCUGUGGAUGUCGUUGACUCAGAUGUGCCUCCGUUGGGGUGGGAGAACCCAGGGAUGGGGGUCAGCAAGCCAGGAACUCCGCAGGGUUUGUUUUUAAAACUCUGCUGGACAGAAGUGGAGGAGGAAAGAAUCUAACCAUAUGACUUUUAUAAAAAUCCUUUCACUUUUCCCCUCCCCAUUUGAAAACUCUUUUUAAGAGUGAAUGUAGCUGAAACACAACUGUGUCCAGCCAUUUUCCUGUCUCCACAUUCUUCCAGAUGUGUGACAGAGGAGGGACUCUGCUCAAUUCCAGUUGUGGGUCCCCUUGGAGUUUACAUCACUUGUUUUUCAAUUCUUGGUUUUCUGUUCCCUUCUACCAAAACCCAGCAUAGGACUCAGUGUACACUUACUUUAAAACAAAAACUCACAUUUCUUAGCUGCAGGUGAUGGCCUCAGUCAUUUUAAUACAGCCUGGAAUGAGUUUGCUUAUUACCCAGUCACUUUCGUAGUGAAUGUUCAAACCCCAAAGCAAAUGUUUGCAUCUCCUUGUCCAUAAAGGAGAAAGCCAGGUUAUAGGAGAAAGAGAGAGAAAGGCGCAUGUCUGUUUGCACAGAGAGAGGCAAUUUUGUCUACCUUUCGAGAAUCAGUUAUAAACAGAAGGGCCUCUUAGGAUUUUGAGCUCUCCUGACAAUGAAGGAAAAGCUCUCUUGAGUAUACAAGUUCCACACUCAUUACCUUUCAGUGGUGACCCAUCACCCACUACAAUUUGUUGAAGGAAGGGAGUGUCAGAGAUAUGCUUUAAAGUUGUACUUUAGGCUGAAAUUCUCUCUGUAUUUGGACCUGCAGAUGUUGUGUACAGAACCGAUGCAUGGCAGGGUCAGGAAGCUAGGAGAGUGAAGGCGCUUGUGGAGACAGCUCUGUAGCAAAUGAAACACGGAAGCCUCCGGGAAUGUGUUUGUGUCACCAGCAGCAGGCAUUUCCCUGUCCUCCCCACCCCCAGUCUCCACAUCCCCAGCAGCCUCUUCCAGAAGCAUGUCAGGGAGACGGACAGGUGCUCUCCUUCUCGUGCACCACAUCCAAGUCCACCCACCGUGGACGCAGUGUGACUAAAUGCUGGCCUUGAAGAGAAACCCUCAGCCAGCUUGUCUGUUGUCCAGGUCCCUCAGUGUCUCUGGUUUCCCUGCCCUGCAUAAUUUAAGCAUUAGUGCCAAAUACAUCUGUCAUAUUCCUCUCCCUGGAGACUGCGAAAUGUCCAGACUUUUUCAGACUAGUGGAGGGAAGGAAUGUUACAUAACUAAGUGGAGGCCUGGAACUGUCAGGAUUUGACAGGGCUGGACCAGAGACCCUUCCGCCUCUGCCUAGUGUGUCUGUCAGGCAGGCAGCAGCCAUCAAUCCAAGAAUGAGCCAUGGCGGCAAGCACUGUGUGGAGAAAGGAACCCAGCCGAGGUCUGAGUUUCAGACAGAAACUGGGGAGUUGGGACAUCUUCUCUGUGCCAGGCUUCAUUGACACCAUCGCUCCCCACAGCAGCUCCUUGGGGCAGGGGGCUCACCUGUGCAGCCACCCUUACUCACAGUAGCAUCCCAUUCUUCACACUGCAACCCCCCAGCACUGUGGACCCUUCCAGGGAGGUGACAGGAGCCAGCAGACACAUGACAUUCCCAGAAAGCCCCAUCUUAUCCAGACAGGCUUCCCUCCAUACUUCUUUCCACAGUUUUACCCUCAGAAAAAUGUUGGCUGCAGUCUUCCCUUCCUUCACCUCCACCCUGGGGAAGGGUCAGUAACCAAUGCCGAGGGUCGGGGAAGGAGGAGUCACAGGCAAGACAGGGACUCAGCGCAGUGCUCCCGCCAUCAUCGGGGACAGGUGCCAGGGUCAGCUGCAGCUCUCCUUCCGGGAGCAGGGUGUGGUGGCCCUGGAUGGUCCCAGGGAGCAGAGGGAGGCAGGCAGCUGUCACAGCCACAGCGGCUCUGAAUGGCUUGAGCUUUUAGUAUGUGUUCAAGUGCAGGAUACUACAAACUGGUAAAGACUUCCACCAUGUGAAGAAUGUAUGUAAAUUAAAGUUUAUUGUAAUGAAGGUUUUUACUUUUUGCAAUUAAAAGUGUUGGUUGAUAAGAA